AGUUCACCUGCAGAGGAGGCUCCAGAAAGCGGCAUGUCCCCUUUGCUCUUUGGGGCUGGGCUGGUCGUUCUGAAUCUAGUGACGUCUGCCAGGAGCCAGAAGACAGAACCUCUAAGUGGCUCUGGGGACCAGCCACUCUUCCGUGGAGCUGAUCGAUAUGACUUUGCCAUCAUGAUACCUCCAGGAGGCACGGAAUGCUUUUGGCAAUUUGCCCACCAGACUGGAUACUUCUAUUUCAGUUACGAGGUUCAGCGGACAGUGGGGAUGUCACAUGACCGGCAUGUUGCUGCCACGGCACAUAACCCACAGGGAUUUCUCAUAGACACCUCCCAGGGUGUUCGGGGCCAGAUUAACUUCUCUACCCAAGAGACAGGUUUUUAUCAGCUUUGUCUAAGUAAUCAGCAUAAUCACUUCGGUUCUGUGCAAGUGUACCUCAACUUUGGGGUCUUCUAUGAGGGGCCUGAGACUGAUCACAAACAGAAGGAAAGAAAACAACUGAAUGAUACUCUGGAUGCAAUUGAGGACGGCACACAAAAGGUGCAGAACAAUAUCUUUCACAUGUGGCGAUACUACAACUUUGCCCGGAUGAGGAAAAUGGCUGACUUUUUCCUUAUCCAAUCAAACUAUAACUACGUGAACUGGUGGUCGACAGCCCAGAGCCUUGUUAUUAUUCUUUCUGGGAUCCUGCAACUGUAUUUCUUGAAGCGUCUCUUCAAUGUUCCAACAACUACAGAUACAAAGAAGCCAAGAUGCUAAGCUAAGGUGACUAUAGCACCCUGGCUGUUUUCUUCUGGGGCUUAGUCGAAUCAGCUUUGUAAUGUUAUGGGACAAAAAUCAAUUAUCUCAUUAAUGUUUUAGUCUGCUGCACACAUCUAAAAAAGCAAAAUGGCAAUAAAAUCAUAACAGUGAAAAA